AGUCCUGGGCACAACUUCGCAGGAGGAGCAGCGGCAGGUGCUGCAGGCAAGGGCCGCCAUGGCUGGGGGUGUGUGGGGCCGGAGCCGGGCCCGGGAGGCUCCCGUGGGGGCUCUAACCCUGACAGCACUGACUGAAGGAAUCCGGGCCAGGCAGGGGCAGCCCCAGGGACCCCCUUCCGCAGGCCCUCAGCCCAAGUCCUGGGAGGUCAAACCUGAGGCUGAGCCACAGACCCAGGCACUCACCGCCCCCUCUGAGGCAGAGCCUGGACGUGGGGCCACCGUCCCUGAAGCUGGCAGCGAGCCCUGCUCCCUCAACAGUGCCCUGGAACCAGCCCCUGAGGGGCCCCACCAGGUUCCCCAGAGUUCCUGGGAGGAGGGAGUUCUUGCCGACCUCGCGUUGUACACGGCUGCCUGCCUGGAGGAGGCUGGCUUUGCAGGGACCCAGGCGACAGUGCUCACCCUGUCCUCAGCCCUGGAGGCCCGGGGCGAGCGGUUGGAGGACCAGGUGCAUGCUCUGGUGCGUGGGCUGCUGGCGCAGGUGCCCAGCCUAGCGGAGGGGAGGCCCUGGAGGGCGGCCCUGCGAGUGCUGAGCGCACUGGCCCUGGAGCAUGCGCGGGACGUGGUGUGUGCGCUGCUACCCCGCUCUCUGCCCGCCGAUCGGGUAGCAGCCGAGCUCUGGCGCAGCCUAAGCCGUAACCAGCGUGUAAAUGGGCAGGUGCUGGUGCAACUGCUGUGGGCGCUGAAGGGUGCUUCGGGGCCGGAGCCCCAGGCACUGGCGGCCACACGUGCUCUUGGGGAGAUGCUGGCUGUUUCGGGCUGCGUGGGAGCCACGAGGGGCUUCUACCCACAUCUGCUGCUUGCGCUGGUCACACAGCUGCACAAGCUGGCCCGCAGCCCGUGCUCCCCCGACAUGCCCAAGAUUUGGGUUCUGUCCCACCGAGGGCCACCACAUAGCCAUGCCAGCUGUGCUGUGGAGGCCUUGAAGGCGCUGCUCACCGGGGAUGGAGGCCGCAUGGUGGUCACGUGCAUGGAGCAGGCAGGAGGCUGGAGGAGGCUGGUGGGAGCCCACACCCACCUGGAGGGCGUCCUGCUGCUGGCCAGUGCUAUGGUGGCACAUGCCGACCACCACCUGCGAGGCCUCUUCGCAGACUUGCUCCCUCGGCUUCGCAGCGCGGACGACCCGCAGCGUCUCACGGCUAUGGCCUUCUUCACAGGGCUGUUGCAGAGCCGGCCCACCGCACGGCUCCUGCGGGAGGAGGUCAUCCUGGAGCGACUCCUCACCUGGCAGGGAGACCCCGAACCCACUGUGCGCUGGUUGGGCCUGCUGGGCCUGGGCCACCUCGCGCUGAAUCGCAGGAAGGUGCGGCACGUGAGCACGCUGCUGCCGGCGCUCCUGGGCGCACUGGGCGAAGGCGACGCGCGGCUCGUGGGUGCAGCGCUGGGCGCCCUGAGGAGGCUCCUGCUGCGGCCCCGGGCGCCUGUGCGGCUCCUGAGCGCGGAGCUGGGACCGCGCCUCCCUCCGCUACUGGACGACACACGGGACUCAAUCCGCGCCUCGGCCGUCGGGCUCCUUGGGACUCUGGUGCGCCGGGGCCGGGGCGGGCUCCGGCUGGGGCUCCGCGGCCCCCUGCGGAAGCUGGUGCUGCAGAGUCUCGUGCCGCUGCUGCUGCGCCUGCAUGACCCCAGCAGGGACGCUGCUGAGAGCUCAGAGUGGACCCUGGCCCGCUGUGACCACGCCUUUUGCUGGGGCCUGCUGGAGGAGUUGGUCACCGUGGCCCACUAUGACAGCCCCGAGGCCCUGAGCCACCUCUGCUGCCGCCUGGUUCAGCGAUACCCAGGCCACGUGCCCAACUUCCUGAGCCAGACCCAGGGCUACCUGCGGAGUCCACAGGACCCCCUGCGCCGGGCAGCCGCCGUGCUUAUAGGCUUCCUUGUCCACCACGCCAGCCCCGGCUGUGUCAACCAGGACCUGCUGGACUCCCUGUUCCAGGACCUAGGGCGACUGCAGAGCGACCCCAAGCCGGCUGUGGCCGCGGCAGCGCACGUGUCCGCUCAGCAGGUGGCGAUGCUGGCCCGUGCCCGGGGCUGCCCCCGCGGGCCCCGCCUUCUCCGCAUCGCCCCGCGCCCCGCCCGGCCCCCACCAGUCUUCGCCGACAGCCCCUUCCAGCGCCGGAGCGUCGCGGGCCGCUGGGGCUGCUCCGGACCCCGCCGAGCCUGAGGCUCGGGGCUGGGGCCCGAGGGCCAGGGUCCGACUCGGGCACCCCACGCGCAUAGCAGCCUGUCCCCGCCCUGACGGAGGGGCUCCCUGGGCCUGGUGCUGGACGCCAAUGCCCUCCCCCACCCCCCACCCCCGUGACCCCUCUUCAGGCACCCACCACCCUGAUGGUGACAGAGGGGGACAGCCAGCACCCAUCUGUCCCCGUCAGGGCUCUUGUUCUCACAGCCCCCUGGAGCAUGCCCCAUGCCCCAACCUUGGGCCUGGCUCCUGGCCCAGAUGGCACCUGGCCUCUUGAGUCUGCUGGGGGACCCCAAAGUUGGUGGUCCCAUAGCCUGCCCUCCUGGGUCUCCACCUCAUGCCUGGACAGGACGCUGUGGCCUGUCCGGGCCUUGGCCAGCCCUGCAGCUGCACCCCCGAUCCUCAUCCCUCACCCCAUUCCCUGCCAGCAUCCUAAGGCUCCUGGCGGGCAUCCUCUCUGCUCAAAAUUAUUGACCUGUCUCCCGGCCACACCUGCUGUGCCCUCUCAGCCAGGCCAUCAUCACCCCCUGUUCAUUAUGUCAGGCCUCAUGGGAGCCUGGCCUUCUCCAGAAGCUGGCCCCGGCGUCCUCCCAAGCUGGACCACGUAGGCCCCAGAUCACACCUGGGGGUCCAGAUGUAGGGGUCCUGUGUGCACGCCCAAUCAGACCGAGCACUUGUGACACUACCCCAACACCUCUCCCAGGGCUGAAUGAGGAACGCGCCACUGGACACAUGAGGAAGAGGCUGCUCUGGGAGCUACUGAUGCUGUGACCUCACCUCUCUGGCUUUGGGCGGCAGGUCCCUGCACCUAGGAUGCCUGCCUGGAAAUGUCCUUGCAUUCGUGGCCUCCUUCACAGCCUCCUCCUCAGAGAAGCCUCUGCGAGUGCACAGGGAGUGUGUGCAGCCUUGUGAAGGGCUGGGACCACUUGCCCAGACUGGGGCCCCUCAGGCACAGGCGUGGGGUCCUACUGACCUGUCUCCCCAGCUCCCACACAGAAAGCAUCUAAAAUAAACACACGUGGAUGGAAA